GUACAUGUCACAUAUGUAACAGAAAUAAAGCUGAGUGAUACUUAACUUUUUAAUAUGUAAUAUGCUGAUAUUUUCUUAUUUUACUCUAUUUUAUUUUAUGCUUUUUUUAUUUUUAAUGCCAGUCUUGAUGCACUCUAUUGCUUUCAUGACCCACCAAUGGGUCACACAACUCACAGUUGGAACAACACUGCCCUAAAGGGUUAUUAUUGCAGCCUAAGGAGAUAGGAUCCAUUCAAUUACUUAGAUAAGGCACUGAGAGAGUGACACCAGAUGCUGCUGUCUUUGUUUGGAAUCAACCAAAAUGAAUUAUUUAUAAUUAAUCAACCAGUAUGCAUUAUUUGUACCUUGCAUAUAGGAGGUUCAGCUCCACCUGAGGCUUUUUGGGUAGCUGAGAAGACAAAACACUUGCUGUAUUCACAGAGUCAUGUGCCAUUAACUGAUCUUCCAAAACAUUAACUGAGCACUUACUAUGUUUCAAAUACUGUGUGAAAGCCUGAGGUUACAAAGAUAAGUCACAGACAGCUGUAUGGGAGCAACACACAAGAGAGCCAAUAUUUAAGUCCAACACGGCAAAUGUUAUGACAGAUCUGAGAACAGAGCAGAGUGUUCUGGGAGCACUGAACAAGAGUUUGUUAAUGGCAGCAGGGAUUAUGGAAGGCUUCCUGAGGGAAGUGAUUUAUGCUGAGUCUUGAAGAACAGGCAGGAGUUGUCUAGACAGAGUGAGAAAAAGCAAAGAAGAUAGAAUAGCUCAUGUGAAGACAAAAAGGCAAGAGACAGUAGAUGAAACUCACUCAGAAAAAUUGAAACAUGGACACAUGGAAGAAGAUGAGUCAGAAGAGGAAGCCAAGGAGAUGUGGGCCAUGAUGGUCUGAGUGCCAGGCCCGGUUGUUUAGAGGAUGGGGAGCCAUGAAGACUUUUAAGCAAGAUGACUCAAAUUUGCUUUUAUAAAAUACCACUUUGCAGCAAGGUAGAGGAUGGUUUGGGGGUGAGCAAAGCUGGUGAGAGAACAAUUAGGAAAAUGACAGAGAUACUGGUUUAUGAUAGAGCUGAUUCUGGAUACCCACAUUUUUUGGCAAAGAAAUCACACCCCUUCUGAAAUCACUGGCAUGUGAAAAUUUUAGUUCAGGGAUUUUUAUUCCAGUAGGUGAAAGAGACAAAGUAUUCCUGCAAGGAAUUGUCUCAUAAGUAUUGUAGAAGAAUAAUACAUAGAAAUGUCCAAUUUGAAUUGCCUCAUUUAUCCUUCCUCAUCAGUAAAAGUUGAGGCCCUCACAGCCUGCUCUCUUUUCCCAUUUUUCUUUUUUCUUGGCGGGGGCAGGGAGGAGGUGUGGCUUAUUUUCAUUUAUUGACCUGACUAAUGGGUACGUAGGUGAUCAUUCUGUGAGAAAUCAUUGAGCUAUACAUUCAUGUUUUACCUGCUUUCUGUGUGUUACAAUUCAAUUUUCUGAUGUUUUACAAAUUGCUAUUACAAUAUAAGUCUAUUUGAAACUUAUGAAAAGGAAAAUAGGCAAAUGUCACAUAUCUUUUCUGGUUGCGGCCUUGCACCCUACUGCCCUCAGGGAAACUUGAUCUGACUUCACCAAGCAACCUUUUGGAAGUAGUCCCUUCUGAGCCUGUCCUUUUCCAUAAUGUCCAAAUUCUUAAUGAAUGCAGUUGAUAAACCUUGUAAUAAUGUGUCAACAGCAUGAUACUUCUUUCAUAGAAUAUGCAUGAACUGUGUAGAAACAAUGCAUUGUCUCAUCAGAGAAGAUGCAAAUUUCAUUCUCUAUGAAAACAAAGAUGGACUGUCAUGAGAAUGCCAUCAGGGCACUGAAUAUGAGGAGAGAAGAAAUAAGAGACAAUCAGGGGCAUUUGUAAUUAUGAAGAAACCACUGUUUUUUUUUUUCUGUAGACCUCCUCUGUGGACAACCACUAUUUUUUUGAUUCAACUUUUAUUUUAGAUACAGGGGGUACAUGUACCAGUUUGUUACAUGAGUAUAUUGCAUCCAGGAAGUGAGCAUAAUACUCGAUAGAUAGUUUUCAACCCAUGCCUCCCUCCUUCCCUGACCCCUCUAGUAUUCUGCAGUGCCUGUUCAUAUGUUCCCAGUUAUGUUCAUAUGUUCCCAGUGUUUAGCUCCCUCUUUUAAGUGAGAAGAUGCAGUAUUUGGUUUUUUAAUCUUGAAUAAAUUUACUUAAGAUUAUGGCUUCCAGCUCCAUCCAUGUUACUGCAAAAGACAUGAUUUUUUAUGGCUGCAUAGAAUUACAUUGUAUAUAUGUACCACAUUUUCUUUAUCCAAUCCAGGCACCCAGGUUGAUUCUAUGUCUUUGUUUUUGUGAAUAGCAUAGCAAUGACCAUAUAAGUGCACAUGUCUUUUUGGUGUAAUGAUCUAUUUCAUUGGGUAUAUACCGAGUAAUGAGAUUGCUGAGUUGAAUAGUAGCUCUGUUUUAAGUUCUUUUAGAAAUCUCCAAACUGAUUUCCACAGUGGAUGAACUAAUUUACACUCCCACCAACAGUGUAUGAGAAUUCCCUUUUCUCAGACUGUAAAAGUCCUAAAUGAAAACCUAGGAAAUACCCUUCUUGACAUCAGCCUUGGCAAAGAAUUUUUAGCUAAGUCCUCAAAAGCAAUUGCAACAAAAACAUAAAUUGAUGAGUGGGACCUAAUUAGACUACAGAGCUUCCACACGGCAAAAGAAACUAUCAACAGAGUAAACAGACAACCUACAGGAUGGGAAACAAUAUUCACAAACUAUGCAUUUGACAAAGGUCUAAUAUCCAGAAUCUAUAAUGAAAUUAAAUGCAUCAACAAGCAAAAAAAUAAAUAAUCCCAUUAAAAAAUGGGCAAAGGGCAUGAAUAGAACAGCAUUUUUUCAUAUGCUUAUUGGCUGCUUGUAUGUCUUCUAAAGAAAAAAUGCUCAUCAUCACUAAUCAUCAGAGAAAUGCAAAUCAAAACCACAAUGAGAAAAACAACAGAUGCUGGCAAGGCUGUGGAAGAAAAGGGAAUGCUUAUACCCUAUUUCUUUAUUCAUUUGUAUCUCCCUUAAAUUUCAUCUCUAGGUAAGUGCUCCCCCAGGUGAGAACAGGCCUCAUUUUAUUUUAUUGGUAUUUCUCUUCUUUCCACAGGCUAAACUUCUUAGAGGGAAAGAUGGAGGAGUAGGGAGCACCCACGUAUGUUUCUGCACAUAAGAAAAAAUAACCUGAAAUUCACAUCAUAAUGUCAGGUCCAGCAUCUUCAAAUCCUUACAAAAAAGAUGCCCAGUUACAAUUCAAAACCAUGAACACAGAAUGACUAUUUGUUAAGGCCAAUGUGGAAAGGAGAGUGGUAAGGAGCAAACCUUAAUAUAUCAUAAAAGUAGCUUUUAGUAAUCAUUGGAAAAUCCUUGAUUCAAUAUGACAAAUUUAAGUUUUUUCAUCUCUAGUGCCCACACAAAAUGCUUAGUAUUCAGAAGCAUUUUAUCUAAGCUGGAAGCACUCUAAUGACAAUUCAGAAGCCUUUACUCUCUCCUCAGGAAGCAUUUCAGUUAGGACAAUGGUGCAGAACGAGAUGCUGGUGUAAUAGGUAAAGAAUUUGCAUGAACAAAGCAUAAAUAGACGCACAGUCAGGUUUAGCCUGAAGUCCAAAAGCUCAAAUGCUUUUUUUAACCUCUUCUCUUUCAGACAGAAUUUUUCACAUUCCAUUUCUGAAAACUUUUCCAAACAAUGUGAAAGCACAGUAAGGAAAGUGAAUAACAAAACACUGUAAGUAUUUGCAUGCAAGGAAACUCAGAAGUCGUAUCUUGUUCUGUGUGCACCUUAUUAUCAGCAUCAAUUAUUUUCUUUUGAUACAAGUCUUGGUUACGGAGCUGUUGCAAAGCAACUUUUAAUAGUUUUAAAAUGGGAAUUUUUUCUUUGCAAUUGGCAUCAAGUUGAUCAGGUAUGUCUUUCAACUGUUUAAAAAAACUAUUUUAAAAUGUUCCUUAAUAUUUAUUCUACAAUUGUAUUAAAGCCUCCUCAAAAAUUAAAAUUUUGCAGGUAUGUUGAUGUCACCAAAGGCUGAUACAACUGAUACCUUCAUUUGUAAGAAUUUUCCCUAGUCACAUGGUCAACAUUCCACAAAGAUUAACUAAUUGCAAACGUAGCUUAAAAGUAGCCACUUCCCUUAAAGGAGACUUAGGCUACCUCGACAACUAUGCUCCUGAGCUUAAAAUGAGUCUUAAUGCUAUCGCUACCACAUACACUGGAUGGAAGCUACAUCUCUGUUUUACUGACUAACUUUUAACACUUUUCUGCUAUAAAUGCUGGCUGCCUUGGCAUUUCACUUAUCUUCAACUGUAAAAGAGCAUGCCUCAAAAGAUAAUCCCAGUGUCCCUAUGGCACAUUUACUAAGAUUUAGAAGUUUUAUUAUGCCCCCAUGAGUCCUCCAGACUACAAAACUAGAUGUCCCUCUAAGAUACUUUGCCAAUCUCUUUCUGAAAUUUUCUCUUCUUUUCUUUUCCUAUCAAUCUCCAAGUUAGACAGAUGCUUCAGGUUGGUACGGUGGAAUGACCCUGGACUUUGGGGUUCCAUUCCAAGUAUAUGAAUCUUUGGAAGUAACCUUCCUGUAACAGAGUAUCGCUGGCAAAAUUUAUCCCUUUUGAGACCUUUCUCCUCAUCUGUAAGGAACAGCAGAAAUACCAUUUGGCUUUCAGAACCAUGAGAAUGAAGGAAGUUGCUAAGCAAUGCGACAACACCAAGGUUAUUCUUCCAUGCUUGCUGAGAGUGAACUGAGUGGCUGGGACUAUGAAUAUGGUUUCUGCUUACCCAAGACACCCCGAUGUGCUCCUGAACCAGAUGCUUUUAAUCCCUGUGAAGAUAUUAUGGGCUAUGACUUCCUUAGGGUCCUGAUUUGGCUGAUUAAUAUUCUAGCCAUCAUGGGAAACAUGACUGUUCUUUUUGUUCUCCUGACAAGUCGUUACAAACUUACAGUGCCUCGUUUUCUCAUGUGCAAUCUCUCCUUUGCAGACUUUUGCAUGGGGCUCUAUCUGCUGCUCAUAGCCUCAGUUGAUUCCCAAACCAAGGGCCAGUACUAUAACCAUGCCAUAGACUGGCAGACAGGGAGUGGGUGCAGCACUGCUGGCUUUUUCACUGUAUUCGCAAGUGAACUUUCUGUCUACACCCUCACCGUCAUCACUCUAGAAAGAUGGCACACCAUCACCUAUGCUAUUCACCUGGACCAAAAGCUGCGAUUAAGACAUGCCAUUCUGAUUAUGCUUGGAGGAUGGCUCUUUUCUUCUCUAAUUGCUAUGUUGCCCCUUGUCGGUGUCAGCAAUUACAUGAAGGUCAGUAUUUGCUUCCCCAUGGAUGUGGAAACCACUCUCUCACAAGUCUAUAUAUUAACCAUCCUGAUUCUCAAUGUGGUGGCCUUCUUCAUAAUUUGUGCUUGCUACAUUAAAAUUUAUUUUGCAGUUCGAAACCCAGAAUUAAUGGCUACCAAUAAAGAUACAAAGAUUGCUAAGAAAAUGGCAAUCCUCAUCUUCACCGAUUUCACCUGCAUGGCACCUAUCUCUUUUUUUGCCAUCUCAGCUGCCUUCAAAGUACCUCUUAUCACAGUAACCAACUCUAAAGUUUUACUGGUUCUUUUUUAUCCCAUCAAUUCUUGUGCCAAUCCAUUUCUGUAUGCAAUAUUCACUAAGACAUUCCAAAGAGAUUUCUUUCUUUUGCUGAGCAAAUUUGGCUGCUGUAAACGUCGGGCUGAACUUUAUAGAAGGAAAGAUUUUUCAGCUUACACCUCCAACUGCAAAAAUGGCUUCACUGGAUCAAAUAAGCCUUCUCAAUCCACCUUGAAGUUGUCCACAUUGCACUGUCAAGGUACAGCUCUCCUAGACAAGACUCGCUACACAGAGUGUUAACUGUUACAUCAGUAACUGCAUUAUUGAAUUGUUCUUAAACCUGUAAAAAAAAAUUACCUGUACCAGUAAUUUUAACAUAAAGGGUUGGAUUUAGGAAAUUAUUUAUUUUUAGGUACAUUAGGCAAGAGACCUCUACCUAGUAGAAAGUGUAGUCUAUGACCACUGCCACACUAAAAACUAUUUGUCAUUGUUACAUGGCAUAAAUACUGAAGUUGAGAGUGUUUAGAAAUUUUUAUAGAAAUUUUGACACAGUAAUUUUGUUUGAUGAAUCUUUUAAAAAACUGAGGAGGUAUUUUGCAUAUCUUUUUUUUCAUUUUCGUAAUUUGUAUUGCAUUCUAUAAAAAUAUUAGUUCAUAACAGAUCAGAAAUUUAAAAUAACUGGCCUUUUUCCUCAGGUAGUUUGAAAAACACACUCUAGAGAUGCACUGUCCAAUCCGGUAGCCACUAGCCACAUGUGGCUAAAUUAAAAUUAAAUAAAAUGAGAAAUGUAGUUUCUCAGUUGCACUAGCCACGUUUCAAGUUCUCAAUGGCUACGUGUGACUAGUGCUUACCAUACUGGACAGCACAGACACAGAAUAUUUUCAUCACCACAGAAAGUUCUAUCUGUUCUAUUAUAGAGACUUUUAUCUAUGCCCUAUCUGGAUUCUACUUAUUUAUAAUUUAAGGUAAACAUCUGAAAGCACAUUUCAGCCUAUUUGCUUAGUGAAACAUUAAGCUGUAGACUGUAAACUCCUCGUGAGUAGGAACCCUGUCUCAGUGCAUUUUGUUUUCCUGCUUCCUACCUCAAGAUCUUGGCAAUGGUACACUACAAAUGUGCUGAGUUAGAAUUACUCUGAAGUUAUGAAACAUAUAAUGAAAACAAUUUUUUCUAGAGCUUAUAUUUUUAUUUGAAUGAAAUAAAAUGUUUAAAUAUUUAAAAAUAA